UAAAGGGUUUAAUUUCCUUAUCCCCUCCUCCCGUUUCUUCUCUCUCCUCUCUCUCUUUCUCUCUCUUCCCCUCUCCCUCUCUCCUCUCUCUCUCUCUCCCUCUCCCUCUCUUUUAUCUCUCUCUGUCUCUUUUGCCUACAUAAAUAUUACCAGGCUUUGAAGGAAGGUCUGACUUGCUUCCUAAUCAUCAGCCGACCCCAUCCUCUGUAGAGUGGGAAACAAUAAUGGAGAGAGAGAGAGAGAGAGAGACGGAGGAGGCUGGUGCUGGUGGCCGGCGGCGAGGCUGGGUGCAGGGGGCGAUGGUGGAGGUGACAGGGUGGCUGGCGCGGCUCCGGUCACCCAGGCAUUGUCAGCGCGCGGGUCCCCAUGGCCCCGCGGAGCCCAGCCCGCUCUCCCCUGCCAGGGGCAUGCCGCGCCUCCGCUGCCCACUGACGGCGCCCGGAGCGCCUCCCCUCCUCCUCCUCCUCCUCCUCUUCUUCUCCUCCUCUUCCUCCUCCUUCCUUUCCUUCUCCUUCUUCUUCUCCUCCGCCUCCCGCUCCUGCUCCGCGCUGGCUCUCCCAGAGUCCGGAGCCUGGGCUGCCUCCGGCGGGGCGCUCCCUCCCCCCCACCCCCCACCCCGCGCUCUAAGUGCUGCCGCCGCCGCCGCCGCCGCCGCCGCUGCCGCAGGGCCGCCCGCGGGCGCCGCCGCCGGGGCUCCGACUGCUGACGCCGCCUCCCGCGGAGCUCCGGGCCGAAUCGCCUGGGCUGGGCCUCCCGAGAGCCACAGUCAUCUUCAGUCCGCGGGCUAAGUUGCCGCCAUCUUCGUCCUGGAGAAACACUUUUUUGGGGGGAGCGCUGGCUUUUGCGUCAUCUCCUCCCGCGCCGAGCUCGCUCCAUCCUGGCGCAGUGGCGCCGGCUCGGCCCGGGAGGAGGGAGAAGGCGCGCGGGGGCGGGCGGCGGCGGGGCCGCGGGGCCCGGGGGCCCCCGCCCGGCUCCCCGGGCUCAGGCGCCUGCUCUUUCCUUUCUGUCCCCCUGUCCACGAUAUUUUGUUUUAAUCACUGAAGAGAAAAAUAAAAGUCAGACUGCGGACGGCAUGGCCGGUGAGGCUCCUCGCGGCCGCGCCGCCCGCACGCUCUGGCUCCGGGAAGCGUCCGAGUUGCAGGCGCCCGGGCAGAGGUCUCUACUGGUGCGAGGGUCUGGGCAGAGUCCUCUCAACUAAGGACCGAGCCACUUCGGAUGGAAGGUGGGGGUCCGCGGAGGAAGCUCGAAUUGGCUAGAGGAGGGAUGAGGUGACAUUUGGUCUCUGAAUGCGUCUCGGAUCCCGGACCGCGAGAUCCAUCGCUCCCAGUGCGUGCAGUUAUUCCGUCCUGCUGUGUGACACGGGAGAAUGGCGCGCACGCCUGUGCACCUGCAUCGACCGUGUAGCUGCCUGGGUGACAGCCACCCAUUUGUCUAUGUUUUCUUUCCUAUUCUAAAGUAAACGAUUAGAAGUGGCCUCAUAGAGUCUUAGGAAGAAACAGUAAGCCCUGUGCCACCCGGGGUCACUGCCUAGCCCUGCCCUCCGCGCGCACCGUCCGCGUCUCCGAGGGCUCCUCCUCGGACCUGGACCCUCUGGAGCGGCUUCGACCCUCCCUCUGCCCCCGCUGCCUGCGUCCAGACCCCCUCCCGGGUGGGCUCCUCCGAGGACCUCCGCAGCCGCGGGCGAGCUGGGUGCCUGCGAGUCGCCGCCGCAGUCUGAGCCUCUGGUGCCCCUUAGCGUUGGCUCUCGGAGUUCUGAGAAGGGAAAGGAGACAGACACUCUGGGAAAAUCUGGGGUCACCUCGAUUCCGGCUCCUACGCUGGAUGCCGUGGGCAAGCAUCGGUCUCCUUUGAUCUGAAGAUCCUGCCCACUCCGCCCCUUGCCCCUGCCAGACCCGCGGGAGCAGCAGGUGGCGUGGGUGCCAGACGCUGCCGGUGCGCACCGAGUGCAGCGCUGCCCCGGCUCGCCCCGGGGGUCGCGUGGGACAGCGGUUUGCGGUGUCGCCCUCUCUGCGGUGCUUUCCAAGGACCCUCAUGCCCCGCCCGGGUGCACAUUCACCACAUGGGUCUUACUAGGUGACCUCUUUCUAAGUAAAAUGCAUUGAGAAACCAAAGGGAUGGGGCAUCCGUAUCCAUUUUCCUUUAAGGAGCGCUGUGGGUGUUGGGGAUGCGGGAGAAGUAGGUGUUUUUUAAAGAGAAAAUUGCAAAACCUCUUGGGCAGGAUUCGACCUACUAGCCUCUUCUGCUGCAUAAUAAGGUACUGUAUACACUAAAUUUUACCCCUAAAAAUUUUCAGUUCUUACCAACUAUAGGUAAUGAUCAUCCAAAAGCCGCGUCCUGUUUGAUGGCUGGUUUACUCAAGUGUCAUGUAGUGUUUUAAAAGACGAUUUGUGUAAGUAGAUCAUUCUAGUACUUUCGAUUUCAGUGUGUUGAAUUUCUGAGUAAUGUCAGUUUUUCCUCAUAAUACAGACAAAAUUAUUAUUUAUUAACCAGAUUGUUUAUUAAUCAGGACUGUACUGUACAUGCCACAAUAUUUCUUAACUAAAUACGAGUGCAUACAUUCUCGCUGACAUAACUAUUAUUAUACAAGUACAGUUUGUGCAUUGUAAAAAAGGUGUAAAAAUCAGAAGAGCAAUUUAAAAAGUCAUGGUGAUAUCAACACCCAGAUAUAAUCAGUAUUUUCAUUUUACAGCAUCUUCCUAACAUUUUUAUUUUGUAUUACUAAUUUCCUGUUUUGUGAUAUUCACUAGUCCAGCAUUUUCGAAGGAUUGAAGUAUGAUAGAAUACACAUCCACACUUAUUAGAUAAUAAUAUAUUUCCCUUCAAUAAUGCAUUAAUUUUAAUCAGACACAAACAUUUUAAUGGUGGCUGAGAUUAUUAGCAUCCAAUGUCUUACUCUGCAUGUGUGAUUAAAUCAGAAAGAGAACGAAAACUAGGGGAAAUAAAAUAAACAAUAUAAAUUUAAAGGUUCAUAAUUAUCAAACAAGGAACCGAAGCAAAAGAAGACUCUGUGACUUAUCUUAUUACUAUUCAGAUCUAGUAAAAAUCAUGUCUCAGAAGGUAGUUCAGUGAUACUUAGUAAAAGUCUUAUAUACUGCAUUAAAAUAAUAGUGUUUAAUCUAUUUUUACUUUAUGUAACAGACUAUAGUUAAUUAUUUUUAAGUAAGCUGGGCCUUGCCUUCCUCUAAUGUUUCUCAUGAAUUAGGAUAUUUUUAUAAAAGACAAUUUUAAGGACGCAAGCCCACUGAAAGUAAACUGUUGAGAACCAAUUUGACUUUUGUUUGUUGUGUGUUGGUUCUAGAAUGAACUGUUGGAAGACAGAUAAAAGACCAAGUCUGGCCUCUUGAAGCUUAGUCAAGGGGCAGAUAAUACUAACUAGGCCAACAAUUACAAUACAAGGUAAUCUGUGAAGAUUAGCAUGUUUUGAGACUUCAGAGUAGAGCAGUAAACUCCAGUUGGAUUUUAAGAGGGACUAGGGAUAGAUAGGAAUUGGGGACAUUUAACGGGAGCAGAAAGAAGUCUUCUAGGGAGGAGAAAAGGACAAUUCAGAAGGACAGCAAAUUUCAAGGACUUGGGACCUUGAAGGAGCCCAGGGCACUGGUAGGACUACUGACAGAUAAGUGGGCUGUGUUGUGUGUGACCUGUAUAUUGGGAGGGGGUAAGGGAAGAGGCUGGAGAGAAAGGCUGGGGCUCUGUUAUGAAUGAUACUGUAUAAUACUCAAAGGAAAUUGGCUUUUCUCCUGAAAGAGAUGGAUUCAUUAAGGAAAUUUAGAUUGUGACUUCAAUGUUCGUUUUCAUGAACAUCACUGUUCACUAAAAUCAAAACGAGAAAUAUGUUUGGAGAAGGCGUUAACUAGAUUAGUAAAUGUUGAUUCUUAUUAGCUUAUCAGCUAAAAUAUUGCAUAGUGGCAAGGAAGAGCAAAUAGCUUGGCUGGAAUGUAGGUUUCAUUUAUAUCAGGAAAAUCAGGCUGUGGAGUCUAGAAACUCCUACGUAGGUUUUACCUAGGAGUGUGACUAAUGGAAUAGAGAAGUUUAAUAGCACCAGCACAUUUCAGAAGGCUGCUGAAUAGUAGACAGUUGCAAAUACAUUAUAUUGAGGGAUCUGCUAACAGGAUGUACUCUGAACAAGAAAACAUUGCAGAAACAAUCUACAUGUAUAUCAUAGCUCCAGGAUUACUGUUCAGGGGGUCAUUUAUGUUUAUAACCUUCAAAAAUUCAAAGCUCUUACGUUAUUUGAUCAUGCUUAUUUUCAUGGGAAUCAGUGCUUUUAUUCCUAUUUAAAUGGCUAAAGUUGUUAUGCAUUGGGAGAUGGGUUUCUUAUUCUGCCUUUACGUUAUAAAAACAACAAAAUGAUAUAUUUGUUGUCUUCUCAAGUAUUUAUCCUUAUCCCUUAAAAUUAACAUCUGCCAAAUAAUUUUACCAAAGAAAAACAGGCAAAUCCAGAAUAUCUUCUUAUCUAGUGAAGGCCAUUGCUUAAAUAUGUCCACUCCAUAAAUCAAGUAAAUAACAACCCCAAGAUAUUUUCUUUUUUCACACUGAAUGCAUCCUGAAAACACGAAAUUAGGUACACCCUUUGUUGUUCUCAUAUACUGUUUAUGUGACACAUAUAAGUGAAAAUGGAUUAUGCUCUUAUAUACACAUUAAUCUCAAAAAAGACUUUUGUGCUUUUAGAAUUCACAGGCAAUGUGCAAAUUCUUGAUGAGCAUGUCUACAUUUUCUACUUAUUUUUGUGGUUGUAGUUUUGAGAUGGAGUCUAGCUCUGUCCCCUGGGCUGGAGUGCAAUGGUGCGAUCAUAGCUCACUUCAGUCUCAAAAUCCUGGGCUCAAGAGAUUGUCCCACCUCAGCCUACCGAGCAGCUAGAACCGCAGGUGCAUGUCACCAUGUCCAGCUAAUUUUUAUUUUUACUUUUAUUUUUUGUAGAGAUGUGGUCUCCCUGUAUUGCCCAGUCUGGCCUAGAACUCCUGGCCUCAACUGAUCCUCCUGACUCAGUCUCUCAAAGUGCUGGGAUUACAGGCAUGAGCCACCACACUGGCAAAUGUCUACAUUUUUUAAAACAAAUUAAACAUAAAGAGCUCAUAAAGAAUAGUCAAAGUUUAUUUGUGGAAAAAUAUAAGACUGAUCUAUAAGCUUUUAAUUCCACUAUAAUUUGUGAAUGUAAACCUCUCUUUAAGAUAAAAGCAGAUUCUAGCAUCAUGAGGUACCUGAGGGCUCUAGUUAGUUACCAAGAUGGGAAAUGUGCCUGGGGCUUUCUGUAAUUGCAUUUCCACCUUGAUUUGAUAGGGUUGAUUUGGCAAACUAGCAUUUUCUCUCUAUCUGUGUACUUCCACCAUGCUCCAGCUCAGUGAUUUUCUAAUGUUGGUGGGCAGAGAAUCAAGUAGAGACUUAGUCAACUUGGGCCCCUCUCCAGAGACCUGCCUCAGUAGAACUAGGCUGGGGUCCAAGGAAACUAUUUUUAACAAGAACCCCUUAGUAACUUUUUCUAACCUAAGAACGCUUCUACCUACAGUAUUGGCACUGCUGGAUAGAGUGGCCGGUGUGAGUCAAAUGAGGGUGCAUGCUCUAAAUUCUAAACCAGUAUCAAGAUUCAUCUGUGGAGAAUAUAGUGUUAAAUAAUGUUAUUUGUGAUUAAGCAUUAGCGUGUAUAGAAUUAAGUCAUGAACACUUUUCAUAGAAUGCAAACAAUGUAUACCCCACAUGACAUUAAAAAUCUAUGUCAUCAUUGUCAUCAUCAAAAUUACUAUUUGACAAACUCUUUUAAGAACGUGUGUACAUACACACCAUUUGCAAGCAACAAAAGUGACAGAGGGAAAACGCUUCACUCAAGAUACACAGAACGAGGCCCAUAUGGAGAAAUGGACAGAAGUUACUGACAAAUAAAAUAAAAGAUUUGAACAGUAAGAAAAAUCUGCCUGUGUCUACACAGAAAGUUGGCUAUUAUAAAGAUGAAAAUUCUCCCUAAAUCAAGUUACAUAUUCCUGAAAACAAAACGUGAUUAUUUUUCCUGAAAGAAACUAUCCUCCAAAACAGAGGGAGCCAUUUUAUAUUUGACUUCUUACAAAAUCUCUCAUAACGUGGGGGCCUCUCUCUAUUUUAUUUCAAACUUCAUUUUGGGAAGACACAAAGGCUCUUGAAAUGAGAGCCACCAAUGUUUGUUUUAGAUGCUUAUAAAGCUUACCUCAUGGAGCUGUUAACAUAGCAAAAUAAAUUUUUUAACAAAGGAAAAUUUGGUAACUAUUUCUGGGGUAAAGAUUUUACAAUAGCAAGUAUUAUCACUAGACAUUACUUUAAAUGUGGAUUUUUUUAAAUCAUGGUAGAAAACAAUAUAAAAAGUGUUCAUGUGGCAGUUGUUAAGAAUACACAUCUUCAGGGUUUUUUAAUAUAAAAAGGGGAAAGAACAGUCUCAUUAUUAUAUGCAUAGUUUCUCUGAUUUGGUACAAAAUUUCCCAGUGAUGUCAUUGUGGAAUGAUCCAAGUGUUGCCUGUCAGCAGAGAUAGGAGUGAAGUUGAUGAUGAUGGUUAGAUGGCCUCACAAGGGACUCUAGUGAUAGUAAAGGUUCCAGUGGCAAACACACAAGUGAAAAGUUUGAAUAUAGUUUCAUAAUGUUUGAGAGUGUAAAAAAUGCAUUUUUAAAUUAAUGCAUUACUUUCUGUACUAUUUUAAAUAAGUGUGUAUCUAAAUAAACACAUAAAAUGUUAUGAGUAAA